CUCCGCAGAAGCCGAGCGCCAAACUCAAACUUUAUCAGGACCCGGACCUCUCAGGCUAAUCCCGAGGGCCGGGCCUGUUGGGCUUUUCUGCACACCAGCCGAGGCAGCGAGCCAACAUGAGCCAAGUGCUGUUCCACCAACUAGUCCCGUUGCAGGUGAAAUGCAAAGACUGUGAGGAGAGGAGAGUAAGUAUAAGAAUGAGCAUUGAACUACAAUCAGUUUCUAAUCCAGUUCACAGAAAGUGUUCUCUGGUACAUAAUUUUGGUGUACUUUUUGUGAGCUCUAGCUGUUAUGAUGGUCUCCCACACUAUGUACACGUAGCUACCUGGAAAGUGAUCUUUAUGAAAGGUACUUACUUCAUUUGAGACUGAAAACAGUUGGGCUUCCAUAUCAGUGGCCACCUGGCCUAGGAGAGAAUAGGCUCUUUGGAAGAAGCCUGGCAACGUGUUACCUGAUACCCUGGUCUUCUGAGAGACAGAAGCUCUUUUUUCUAGUGUGGAUUAUUGUCAGUUCUGCUGAUAUAUUUGCCACUUUUGAAAUGCCAUACCAGUUAACUUUAAGGAAACUAAAAAUAAAAUUGAAUGUGGUAUGUUCAGUGGUAAAGAAAAUUUUCAUCAUGUUAUGGUGUAGCAAGGACUGGGUCUAAAUUUCCCCAAGCCUCUGAUAGGAGGAUAUUCCUAAACUUUCAACUCCUAGCACUUGCUUAACUUUUACAGACCUCCAUGUGGCUUUUAAAGAGCGGAAUGUCUACCCCUAUUUAAGAUUCUAACUCUCUAAAGACUAAUAAAAAACCAGCAGCACUAGAAAACAAAGCUGUCUGCAAUAUAACUAUGAUACACUGAUGUUGUUGGAUUUCUUUACUUCUGAGAAGAAAUUACUCAAAAGGCCAGAUCUAGUAAAAACAUUUAAAAACAACAAACUUUCUUUUAGGACUUAGUUAUUCGUCUGACUGAUGACACGGAUCCAUUUUUUUUAUAUAACCUUGUUAUAUCUGAGGAAGAUUUUCAAAGUUUAAAAUUCCAGCAAGGUCUUCUGGUAGACUUCUUAGCUUUCCCACAAAAAUUUAUAGAUCUCCUUCAGCAAUGUACUCAAGAACAUGCCAAAGAAAUUCCAAGGUUUUUGCUACAGUUAGUUUCUCCAGCAGCUAUUUUGGAUAACUCACCUGCAUUUUUAAAUGUGGUAGAGACAAAUCCUUUUAAGCAUCUUACACACCUCUCACUAAAACUUUUACCUGGAAAUGAUGUGGAGAUAAAGAAAUUUCUCGCAGGCUGUUUGAAAUGUAGCAAGGAAGAAAAAUUAUCAUUGAUGCAAUCACUAGAUGAUGCUACUAAGCAACUGGACUUUACACGAAAGACAUUAGCAGAAAAAAAACAAGAAUUAGAUAAGUUACGGAAUGAAUGGGCGUCACAUACAGCAGCCUUGACAAACAAGCAUUCUCAGGAACUGACAAAUGAAAAGGAAAAAGCCUUGCAGGCACAGGUUCAAUAUCAACAGCAGCAUGAACAACAGAAAAAAGAUUUAGAAAUCCUCCAUCAACAAAACAUCCACCAGCUACAAAACAGACUGUCUGAGUUAGAAGCGGCUAAUAAAGACUUAACCGAAAGAAAAUAUAAAGGAGACUCCACUAUUAGAGAACUUAAAGCAAAACUUUCUGGUGUUGAAGAGGAGCUACAGCGGACUAAGCAAGAAGUCCUCUCUUUGCGAAGAGAGAAUUCUACACUAGAUGUUGAAUGCCACGAGAAAGAAAAGCACGUUAAUCAGCUACAAACAAAAGUGGCAGUUUUAGAACAGGAAAUCAAGGAUAAGGACCAGCUUGUUUUAAGAACAAAAGAGGCAUUUGAUACAAUCCAGGAACAAAAGGUGGUUUUAGAAGAAAAUGGUGAGAAAAAUCAAGUACAACUAGGAAAGCUUGAAGCUACAAUAAAAUCAUUAUCUGCAGAACUUCUGAAGGCAAAUGAAAUUAUCAAGAAGUUACAAGGGGAUCUGAAAACUUUAAUGGGUAAGUUGAAAUUGAAGAAUACAGUUACUAUUCAGCAAGAAAAACUCUUGGCUGAGAAGGAGGAAAAAUUACAAAAGGAACAAAAGGAAUUACAAGAUGUUGGACAGUCUCUUCGAAUUAAAGAGCAAGAGGUAUGCAAAUUACAAGAACAAUUAGAAGCUACAGUUAAAAAACUUGAAGAAAGCAAACAACUUCUAAAAAAUAAUGAAAAGUUAAUCACGUGGUUAAAUAAAGAACUAAAUGAAAAUCAGCUAGUGAGAAAGCAAGAUGUAUUGGGACCUUCUACUACUCCGCCUGCACAUUCCAGCAGCAACACAAUCAGAAGUGGAAUUUCUCCUAACCUGAAUGUGGUUGAUGGUAGACUGACUUACCCAACCUGUGGGAUUGGUUAUCCUGUCUCCUCUGCAUUUGCAUUCCAGAAUACCUUCCCUCAUUCGAUAUCUGCCAAAAAUACCAGCCACCCUGGUUCAGGAACAAAGGUUCAGUUUAAUUUGCAGUUUACAAAACCAAAUGCAUCACUAGGAGAUGUUCAGUCAGGAGCAACUAUUAGUAUGCCUUGCUCAACUGAUAAGGAAAAUGGUGAAAAUGUAGGGUUGGAAUCCAAAUACCUGAAGAAAAGGGAAGAUAGCAUUCCUUUACGCGGACUCAGCCAGAACCUAUUUAGUAAUUCAGACCAUCAGAGAGAUGGCACUUUAGGAGCAUUACAUACAUCUUCCAAACCCACAGCGCUCCCCUCUGCGUCUUCAGCCUAUUUCCCUGGGCAGUUACCAAACAGUUAAUUCUAGUGUCAUGUUUUACUUUUUAUUGGUAUUUUAGAAACUCAGGUGCUUAAAAAAUAUGUCAACACAAACCAGAUCCUCAAAUAGCAAGUUUCAAAUUUUACUUGAGCUGUUAAAGACUGGAUACUUUAAGUACUGCUUUUAUGGCAGUUUAUAAUAUAGGAACAAAUUUGUACUUGGGGAUUGGUAAAGAUUGUGAGUAAAUGACAUUUUUUGGUUUGUGAACAUGGCGUUUUAUAGAAUAAUAUGAAUUUUAUUAAGCUAUUCUUUAGAAAUUCAGUUCUAAGGAAAGAGUUGAUCCUUAUGAGGGAGAUUCUGAUCAUAUUAAAAAUCUGGGUAAACUAAAACCUGCUCAUAACCUCAUAGUAUGCAACCAAAGAAUACUAAUUCAUUUUAUCACUUUCAUUGGUAAAACUUUUAAAUUCAACACCUGAAAAUCAUGAGGGAAAAUGAUUACCUCUUGAGAUAUAUUAUUGAUGACAUUUAAAGGGAAAAGUCCUAAAUUUACCUUAAAUAACUGAAAUGAAUUAAGCCUUCAUAGCGUAUUUUCCUUGAAGCAUUUAAAUUUGCUAGUGAUGAAUCAAAUAAAUUUGAUAUACUUAAAAUAAUUUGGACAGUUUUUAUGUGACCAGAUUAAGUGCUUUUGUCAUUUGAGCUGACAAGUUUUUAAAACUUCAGUGCUUCCUAAAUGUUUAUACUCAUCUAGUUUUUCUCAAUUUGUAGUUUUAUUAUGCAGUUAAAUCUGUAUCAGUGGACUUUUAAAACUUGGUACUACUACUAAAUCUACUAUAUCAUGAAUAUUCAUUUAUUUUUAUAGUAUCAGAACUUGGGUUGAUUUCAAUGUUAAUAAACUAGGCAAAACAAAUAACUGUUAGAAGGUACAAUUUUCUUCUCUUCCCUGUAACUGAAAGUUUUAAGAAUUGUUCCUUGGGGAAAAAUUUUUUUAAAAUUCACCUAGAAUCAUAGGGCCUCAUUUUGUUUUCUUAUUGACAAACAAUACCUGGUAGCAUUCUCUAAAGAGUCUUCUAGAUCAAUUUUUAUAAAGUACUAAUGCUCAUGUGAUAAUUUAAAAUUAUUUUCAACUACUUUAUUACACAGAUGAAGAAACAUUUCAAGAUAUUGAUGUAAUAACAUUACUGAGUCCCAUGGUAAGAAAGAAUCUUUGCUAAUUUUUUUUUUUUUUUUACGAAGCCAGUAUCUUGAAACUAUUGGCAAUUGCAAGUGUCUUUAAACUAGGGAUCUAAUCUGAAAAUUCAGUAACUAAUAUUAGGCAGUUGAUACUCCCCCACCUCCCCCAUUUAGAUACACUACUGUAUUAGUGAGAAUACUUGGUACAGUAACUUGAAAGCACUUGCUAUUCUGGAAAGAAGCCUCUUGGUGAUUUUGGAAGGAGCUUUAUUGUAAAUACUAUGGAAGGGGCUUUGUUGUAAAUACUAUGUAAUAUAUAUAAAAUAUUGUGACAUGUUUUGGAUGGGAUGCAUGACAUACAGGUAGCUCUCUUUUUUAAAAUAUAGGUAUCUCUUUGCAUAUAUAUACACAAGGAAAGUUGAAUUUUCAGGAGAGAUCAUUCUGAUAUCUUGCAAAUUUGUAUUAAAUGUAUACAGACUUCCAAGUGUGCUAAUUCUUUACCUCCUAAACUUUUAGUUGCAAUUGUUUUGCAGUGUAAAAUUGUACAUGUGUUAAUAAUCAAAAAGUGUUGCAUUUAAUGUUAUUUCUGUAAACUUUGAGCUUUGUUAAUAAACUAUUAUGCAGCAUCUA